AAGUCACUGGUAUCUGGGUGUGUGGGUAUGUUGUGUGUCUGUGUCAGCUUCUGUGCUGUCUGUCACUGUGGGACUUGCCUGUGCAUGUGUGUCCUUUUUCGCAUGUGUGACUUGCUUGUGUGUAUGUGUGUAUGUCUGUUUGUGUCCUGAGGCUCUGUGUGUGUCUUUUGCAACUGUGUGUACCAUUCUUGGUGUGUUUGUUGUCACCAGACUCGUGUGUGUGUGUGUGUGUGUGUGUGUCCUUGCCUGCUAGUGUGUGUGUCCCUGUGUGUCUGGAGGUUUCGGUGUUGCACACUGGGUAUAUCAUGGUGACCAACUGGCCAUGAGUACGUUAGAUCUGUUAAUUGUGGAAGCCCCUGGUGUUGGGUGCCUACCCACCAGUCUCAUGUGUGAGUGUAUCUGUAUAAGUGUGUGUAUGUGUGUGUACUCACGUGUGGCUCUCCCUCUGCCACUGAGUUUCUGUGACCAGGCCCACCUGGUCACUAAGGGAGGGGACUGAUCCCUGGGGUUUCCUCGUUCCUGCUGUGGAGUGAGCUGGGGCUUGGUGAGCAGGCCAGCAGAGGGAGGCUGUAUGGUGCAUGUGUGAUAUGUGUGGUUGUGUGUGUGCGUGUGUGUGUGACAGAGAGGUGUGGUGGUGUCUGGGCAGCUGUACCUGGCUGAUGGGUGGUGUGAGGGCUAUGCGAUGGGACAGUGCUGGGGUAAGCCUGGGAGUGUGUGGCCACGGUAGGAGUGUGUGACUGGUGGGACACAGUCUAUGAAACUGCCGGUGUAUGCUUGGGGAGUGACUGUGAUUGUGGGGAACCGAGAGUGCCUGGGCGUGGGUGUUAGCGGCAGGAGGGGGUGUGACAAGGUGUGUGGUGACAGUGCUGGGAGGGAAGGUGAGAGCCCAGUGUGGGGGUGUGUGUGUGAGUGUGUGGGAGACCAUGAGGAUGUGGGUGUGCACAUGGAGAGGGCUAGAGGGCAAGUCUUGGGGUUUGUAGUGUUGUGACCAAGACCUCGGGCUCUGUACCCAAGAAUUAUUUGGGCUCCAAUACUUGCUUGUGCCUGUUAAGAGCAAGAGACCCAAGCUAGGCCUCUCAAGGCUGAGUGUCCUUAUCUGCAGAAUGGAGAGAGUGAGGACAAAAGUUCCUGUGUUAAAGGUCCUUUAACACAAUCUUGGCCCAUAGUGAGAACACAGCACAUGUGAAGUCUUUUGUUGUCACCACCCCCAGCUAUACGGUUCCCAUUCUCCUGGGAGCUGGGGCUAAAGAAAGCCCAGACAGUAUCCAACCCAAUUUCCUGCCUGUCUGUUGCCCCUUCCCAUCUCCUUGACCAAGCAGCUUGAGGGAGGGGGGAUGCCCAGACAGAGCCCCCAGUACCCAGCCCUGUUCAGCCUGCAUGACAGCCCCUCCCUCACCAGACCUUAGUGUCAGUAGUAGCGAUGGGGGAGACAGGGGUGGGGGAUGAUUCAGAGCUGUGACUGCAGGGCGCUGACACCAUUUAGCUGGCACAGUUUAGAUUAAAAUUAGAAAUAAUUUAAAGUACAGACAAAAAGAUAAAGCCAAGGAUGCCUCUGCCCCCAGGGAAUGGUGAUGGGGGUCUCCAGCUGGGGGAGGGGUUCACAUCUGGGGAGCAGAAUCUUUCUUAGAGGCUUGAGCUGGCCUUCAGAGAAAAUGCUUAGGCCUUUCAGCCAGGAGACACAGAGUACCUUGCUACCUUUGCCAUUUCUUCCUCCCAGGAUAUCUCCAGGCCUCAGUUUUUUCAGCUGUGUAAUGGGCACAAUAGUAAUGUGAGAAUCACCUGAACUGUAAGGCACAAGAGAUUAAAAAAUGUCACUCUUCAGUCUGGGCACGGUGGCUCACACCUGUAAUCCCAGCAUUUUGGGAAGCCGAGGCAGGUGGAUCACUUGGUCAGGAAUUUGAGACCAGCCUGGCCAACAUGGUGAAACCCUGUCUGUACCAAAACUACAAAAAUUAGCUGGGUGUGGUGGCGCGCACCUGUAAUCUCAGCUGCUCAGGAGGCUGAGGCACGAGAAUCACUUGAGACCAGGAGGCAGAGGUUGCAGUGAGCCAAGAUCGUGCCAUUGCACUCCAGCCUGGGCGAUAGAGUGAGACCCUGCCACAUUAAAAAAAAAAAAAAGUCACUAUUCAUUUGGCAUUCUCAACAUGAGUCCAGCACAGGAGCUGGCACGCCACAUCAUUGGAACCUCAGAACCACCUGGGGAGAAGAGGCUAGUAGUUUCCCCAUUAAAAAAACUGAGGCUCAGGGAAAUUGCACCAGGACAUAAAGUGGUGGUACUUUGUUGCACCCUAGGACUCCUAAACCUGCAAGGCAACCUCCCACAGACAGGAGGGUCAGGAACAGGUUUUUGCUGUGUUAUUGGCUUCCUCACCAGGCUGGAAAUGUGCUCAGGGCAGGGACACAGUGUUCCAGCCCCUACCAUGGAGUGGACAAAUAGUGGUGCCCAGGAAAAGUUGGGCCCAACACCACAUUUCAAGGAAGGGAAAGCCACAUCCAGAGAGACCCGAGGUUUUAGGUCCAGGAGAGACUGAACUGGGCCCGUCAGCCAUGCUGGGACUGGUAGACGGGGAGAGCCUGUUUGGCGGUGCCUCCCGGCUCAGCUGUUUCCUCCUGUUCCUACAGGUCUGCAGGGAACUGGCCAGGCAAGGGGGCAGGCCCGUUUCUCCUGGUGGUUGGUGCGUUGUAGCAGCAGCGGGAGCCAGGACUAAGGACAAGCAGGAGCUGGGAGCCCCAGCCCCACUGCAGGCCCCACCAUGGCGCCGUUCCUGCGCAUCGCCUUCAACUCCUAUGAGCUGGGCUCCCUGCAGGCCGAGGACGAGGCGAACCAGCCCUUCUGUGCCGUGAAGAUGAAGGAGGCGCUCAGCACAGAGCGUGGGAAAACACUGGUGCAGAAGAAGCCGACCAUGUAUCCUGAGUGGAAGUCGACGUUCGAUGCCCACAUCUAUGAGGGGCGCGUCAUCCAGAUUGUGCUAAUGCGGGCAGCAGAGGAGCCAGUGUCUGAGGUGACCGUGGGUGUGUCGGUGCUGGCCGAGCGCUGCAAGAAGAACAAUGGCAAGGCUGAGUUCUGGCUGGACCUGCAGCCUCAGGCCAAGGUGUUGAUGUCUGUUCAGUAUUUCCUGGAGGACGUGGAUUGCAAACAGUCUAUGCGCAGUGAGGACGAGGCCAAGUUCCCAACGAUGAACCGCCGCGGAGCCAUCAAACAGGCCAAAAUCCACUACAUCAAGAACCAUGAGUUUAUCGCCACCUUCUUUGGGCAACCCACCUUCUGUUCUGUGUGCAAAGACUUUGUCUGGGGCCUCAACAAGCAAGGCUACAAAUGCAGGCAAUGUAACGCUGCCAUCCACAAGAAAUGCAUCGACAAGAUCAUCGGCAGAUGCACUGGCACCGCGGCCAACAGCCGGGACACUAUAUUCCAGAAAGAACGCUUCAACAUCGACAUGCCGCACCGCUUCAAGGUUCACAACUACAUGAGCCCCACCUUCUGUGACCACUGCGGCAGCCUGCUCUGGGGACUGGUGAAGCAGGGAUUAAAGUGUGAAGACUGCGGCAUGAAUGUGCACCAUAAAUGCCGGGAGAAGGUGGCCAACCUCUGCGGCAUCAACCAGAAGCUUUUGGCUGAGGCCUUGAACCAAGUCACCCAGAGAGCCUCCCGGAGAUCAGACUCAGCCUCCUCAGAGCCUGUUGGGAUAUAUCAGGGUUUCGAGAAGAAGACCGGAGUUGCUGGGGAGGACAUGCAAGACAACAGUGGGACCUACGGCAAGAUCUGGGAGGGCAGCAGCAAGUGCAACAUCAACAACUUCAUCUUCCACAAGGUCCUGGGCAAAGGCAGCUUCGGGAAGGUGCUGCUUGGAGAGCUGAAGGGCAGAGGAGAGUACUUUGCCAUCAAGGCCCUCAAGAAGGAUGUGGUCCUGAUCGACGACGACGUGGAGUGCACCAUGGUUGAGAAGCGGGUGCUGACACUUGCCGCAGAGAAUCCCUUUCUCACCCACCUCAUCUGCACCUUCCAGACCAAGGACCACCUGUUCUUUGUGAUGGAGUUCCUCAACGGGGGGGACCUGAUGUACCACAUCCAGGACAAAGGCCGCUUUGAACUCUACCGUGCCACGUUUUAUGCCGCUGAGAUAAUGUGUGGACUGCAGUUUCUACACAGCAAGGGCAUCAUUUACAGGGACCUCAAACUGGACAAUGUGCUGCUGGACCGGGAUGGCCACAUCAAGAUUGCCGACUUUGGGAUGUGCAAAGAGAACAUAUUCGGGGAGAGCCGGGCCAGCACCUUCUGCGGCACCCCUGACUAUAUCGCCCCUGAGAUCCUACAGGGCCUGAAGUACACAUUCUCUGUGGACUGGUGGUCUUUCGGGGUCCUUCUGUACGAGAUGCUCAUUGGCCAGUCCCCCUUCCAUGGUGAUGAUGAGGAUGAACUCUUCGAGUCCAUCCGUGUGGACACGCCACAUUAUCCCCGCUGGAUCACCAAGGAGUCCAAGGACAUCCUGGAGAAGCUCUUUGAAAGGGAACCAACCAAGAGGCUGGGAGUGACCGGAAACAUCAAAAUCCACCCCUUCUUCAAGACCAUAAACUGGACUCUGCUGGAAAAGCGGAGGUUGGAGCCACCUUUCAGGCCCAAAGUGAAGUCACCCAGAGACUACAGUAACUUUGACCAGGAGUUCCUGAACGAGAAGGCGCGCCUCUCCUACAGCGACAAGAACCUCAUCGACUCCAUGGACCAGUCUGCAUUCGCUGGCUUCUCCUUUGUGAACCCCAAAUUCGAGCACCUCCUGGAAGAUUGAGGUUCCUGGACAGAUCAGGCUAGCCCUGCCCUCCACCCACACCUGCCCGCUCCCCACGAUAAGCACCAGUGGGACUGUGGUGACUUCUGCUGCUGGCCCCGCCCCUGCCCCCAGAGCGUCCUUGGCUGCCGUCUGGCCGGGCUCUCAUGGUACUUCCUCUGUGAACUGUGUGUGAAUCUGCUUUUCCUCUGCCUUCGGAGGGAAAUUGUAAAUCCUGUGUUUCAUUACUUGAAUGUAGUUAUCUAUUGAAAAUAUAUAUUAUAUACAUAGACAUAUAUAUAUAUAUAAUAGGCUGUAUAUAUUGCUCAGUAGAGAAAAACCAUGGGGGACUGGUGAUAUGUUGAUCUUUUUCAAAAAAAUAUAUAUAUGACAAAAAAAAAAAAAAAGGAGCACAAGCUGUUUGAACCACCAGGUUUAUUUGUGUGUCUAAAUAAACACCAAAUAGUACCAA